AGAUUUCCCUCCUUCGUCGCUGUUGCUGCCGCCAUACGCGCUCUCCCUGUUUAGCUCUUCUGUUAGAAAUAGUAUCUUUGUUUUCCUUUGCUGUUCCUCAAUCCCCUACUCUUCACCCCUUGUUUUCACCUAUUUUGCGAGAACCCAUCCAGAUCCCCCUUCCCUUCUUCCCCUGCCGGCCCAGUUAUGGCAGAGAACGAUGUGGACAAUGAGCUCUUGGACUAUGAAGAUGAUGAGGUGGAGACAGCAGCUGGGGGAGAUGGGGCUGAGGCCCCUGCCAAGAAGGAUGUCAAGGGCUCCUAUGUCUCCAUCCACAGCUCUGGCUUUCGUGACUUCCUGCUCAAGCCAGAGUUGCUCCGGGCCAUUGUCGACUGUGGCUUUGAGCAUCCGUCAGAAGUCCAGCAUGAGUGCAUCCCUCAGGCCAUUCUGGGAAUGGAUGUCCUGUGCCAGGCCAAGUCGGGCAUGGGAAAGACAGCAGUGUUUGUCUUGGCCACACUGCAACAGCUGGAGCCAGUUACUGGGCAGGUGUCUGUACUGGUGAUGUGUCACACUCGGGAGUUGGCUUUUCAGAUCAGCAAGGAAUAUGAGCGCUUCUCUAAAUACAUGCCCAAUGUCAAGGUUGCUGUUUUUUUUGGUGGUCUGUCUAUCAAGAAGGAUGAAGAGGUGCUGAAGAAGAACUGCCCGCAUAUCGUCGUGGGGACUCCAGGCCGUAUCCUAGCCCUGGCUCGAAAUAAGAGCCUCAACCUCAAACACAUUAAACACUUUAUUUUGGAUGAAUGUGAUAAGAUGCUUGAACAGCUCGACAUGCGUCGGGAUGUCCAGGAAAUUUUUCGCAUGACCCCCCACGAGAAGCAGGUCAUGAUGUUCAGUGCUACCUUGAGCAAAGAGAUCCGUCCAGUCUGCCGCAAGUUCAUGCAAGAUCCAAUGGAGAUCUUCGUGGAUGAUGAGACGAAGUUGACGCUGCAUGGGUUGCAGCAGUACUACGUGAAACUGAAGGACAACGAGAAGAACCGGAAGCUCUUUGACCUUCUGGAUGUCCUUGAGUUCAACCAGGUGGUGAUCUUUGUGAAGUCUGUGCAGCGGUGCAUUGCCUUGGCCCAGCUACUAGUGGAGCAGAACUUCCCAGCCAUUGCCAUCCACCGUGGGAUGCCCCAGGAGGAGAGGCUUUCUCGGUAUCAGCAGUUUAAAGAUUUUCAACGACGAAUUCUUGUGGCUACCAACCUAUUUGGCCGAGGCAUGGACAUCGAGCGGGUGAACAUUGCUUUUAAUUAUGACAUGCCUGAGGAUUCUGACACCUACCUGCAUCGGGUGGCCAGAGCAGGCCGGUUUGGCACCAAGGGCUUGGCUAUCACAUUUGUGUCCGAUGAGAAUGAUGCCAAGAUCCUCAAUGAUGUGCAGGAUCGCUUUGAGGUCAAUAUUAGUGAGCUGCCUGAUGAGAUAGACAUCUCCUCCUACAUUGAACAGACACGGUAGAAGACUCGCCCAUUUUGGAAUGUGACCGUCUGUCCUUCAGGAGAGGACACCAGGGUGGGGGUGAAGGAGACACUACUGCCCCCACCCCUGACAGCCCCCACCCCAUGGCUUCCAUCUUUUGCAUCACCACCACUCCUGAACCCCCAUUUCUGAUUUGUCAGAAUUUUUUUUUAACAAAACUAAAAAUGAAACACAUGUGUCUGUGGUA